GACAAAUAAGUCCCGCCGGCCGGACGCAGUGGCUCGCGCCUGUGGUCCUAGCUGCUCGCGGUGCUGAGGCGGGAGAAUCACCUGAGCCCGGGAGGUCGGGGGCUGCAUGGAACCGUGAUCGCACCACCGCACUCCAGCCUGGGCAACAGAGCGAGACCCUGUCUCCAAAAAUAAGAAUAAAGAAAAAAAAAAGAAAGAACUGCGGCCCCAUUGGCCUGACUCUCCUGAACAGCCAAACUGUCUCCGACCAGUUACGGAAGAGGCGGCCUUGAGAGGGUAGUGUGCCAUUGGCUCGAUGUCCUGCCCCUCCGAAACCUAAGUCUUCAGCUUCCAAUCAGGACUCAGCUUUGGGAAGAGCGCCACGCGGUGGGCGAGGGGAUGCCCUAGUAAAUUCGCAGAAGCAUGGAUCUCGGAAUCCCUGACCUGCUGGACGCGUGGCUGGAGCCCCCAGAGGAUAUCUUCUCGACAGGAUCCGUCCUGGAGCUGGGACUCCACUGCCCCCCUCCAGAGGUUCCGGUAACUAGGCUACAGGAACAGGGACUGCAAGGCUGGAAGUCCGGUGGGGACCGUGGCUGUGGCCUUCAAGAGAGUGAGCCUGAAGAUUUCUUGAAGCUUUUCAUUGAUCCCAAUGAGGUGUACUGCUCAGAAGCAUCUCCUGGCAGUGACAGUGGCAUCUCUGAGGACCCCUGCCAUCCAGACAGUCCCCCUGCCCCCAGGGCAACCAGUUCUCCUAUGCUCUAUGAGGUUGUCUAUGAGGCAGGGGCCCUGGAGAGGAUGCAGGGGGAAACUGGGCCAAAUGUAGGCCUUAUCUCCAUCCAGCUAGAUCAGUGGAGCCCAGCAUUUAUGGUGCCUGAUUCCUGCAUGGUCAGUGAGCUGCCCUUUGAUGCUCAUGCCCACAUCCUGCCCAGAGCAGGCACCGUAGCCCCAGUGCCCUGUACAACCCUGCUGCCCUGUCAAACCCUGUUCCUGACCGAUGAGGAGAAGCGUCUGCUGGGGCAGGAAGGGGUUUCCCUGCCCUCUCACCUGCCCCUCACCAAGGCAGAGGAGAGGGUCCUCAAGAAGGUCAGGAGGAAAAUCCGUAACAAGCAGUCAGCUCAGGACAGUCGGCGGCGGAAGAAGGAGUACAUUGAUGGGCUGGAGAGCAGGGUGGCAGCCUGUUCUGCACAGAACCAAGAAUUACAGAAAAAAGUCCAGGAGCUGGAGAGGCACAACAUCUCCUUGGUAGCUCAGCUCCGCCAGCUGCAGACGCUAAUUGCUCAAACUUCCAACAAAGCUGCCCAGACCAGCACUUGUGUUUUGAUUCUUCUUUUUUCCCUGGCUCUCAUCAUCCUGCCCAGCUUCAGUCCAUUCCAGAGUCGACCAGAAGCUGGGUCUGAGGAUUACCAGCCUCACGGAGUGACUUCCAGAAAUAUCCUGACCCACAAGGACGUAACAGAAAAUCUGGAGACCCAAGUGGUAGAGUCCAGACUGAGGGAGCCACCUGGAGCCAAGGAUGCAAAUGGCUCAACAAGGACACUGCUUGAGAAGAUGGGAGGGAAGCCAAGACCCAGUGGGCGCAUCCGGUCCGUGCUGCAUGCAGAUGAGAUGUGAGCUGGAACAGACCUUCCUGGCCCACUUCCUGAUCACAAGGAAUCCUGGGCUUCCUUAUGGCUUUGCUUCCCACUGGGAUUCCUACUUAGGUGUCUGCCCUCAGGGGUCCAAAUCACUUCAGGACACCCCAAGAGAUGUCCUUUAGUCUCUGCCUGAGGCCUAGUCUGCAUUUGUUUGCAUAUAUGAGAGGGUACCUCAAAUACUUCUGUUAUGUAUCUGUGAUUUUAUUUCUUCUUUGGGUAUAGGGUUGAGGGGAAAUAAGUUUUGAGUGAGAAAUAAACGUUUUAGCUGAAA